GCAGCCAUUUUGGUGCGAGAGAAACAAUAGGACGGAAACGCCGAGGAACCCGGCUGAGGCGGCAGGUAAAGCUCGCGUCCUAUGGCCCUAGUGCCCGAGGAGCUUUGAGGGAGAUUUUUUCAGGCUACUGGGAAACGGGAUCUCUGAUCAUUGGAGUCUCCCAGGUUAUUUGGGAAAGACUUCUUCCGUGGUCAUUGUGGGGGAAAUCUCCCGGGGUCCCUGUGGAUUCGAUUUCCCUGGGUCAUUUGGGAGGAGGGUUUUUCUUCUGAUCAUUGGGGGAGGGAUUUCCGUGGUUUUGGGGGUCCAGCAUCCUCCCCGGUCAUUGGAGGGGGUCUCCCGGGUUUGGGGGAGGGCAGGAUCUUUCCUGGUCAUUGAGAUCUCCCCGGGUCUUGGGAAGCGCAAGAUCUACGGUGUCAUUGAGGGGUCUCCCCAGGUCAUUGGCGGCCACGAUCUCCCCAGAUAUUUGGCGGGUGGAGGGGUCUUCCCGGAUCUUUGGAUAGGGAGUCAGCUCAGCGCCUCAGGUACUGUUACCUGGGGUCGGCAGAUGUGCAGCCAUUUUGAGUGUUGAAUGCCAUUUGGGCCCGUCAGAUGGUGUUCGAUGAGGGAAUCUACACACUUAACCUUAUUAUAGAAAAAAUGCCUUUAAAUGGAUAAGAGGACACCUUUAUAGUGAUAUUUCCACUCUUUACGUUUGAUUACAGACCGCUUUUGUCUUUUGCAUCCUAAUGGCUUAUUUCAUUUUAGGAUUGUAUUCGUUCUCAUAUAUCAACUAAGCUACACUAGCAGAAAACUUCCUAGGUGACAGACAGGUACACUGUAUGCUAGCCCUGUAUCUGUCUGAGCAGUGGAAUGUGCCAGGAAAGAAGGAGCAACCACUGACUGAUGAACCUUUGCCAGUCUCCCUUCCAAGAGGGAUGCCAGAGCCUUCUGUAAGCUCCUGAGAUGUCACUGGUAUCUAGGCAACAGGGAUGAGCCUGAACCUCCCUGAGGCCAGCUUACUGAGCAGAGCAUCCUGGCCAGAACAAGCCAAGGAGCCAAGACGAGAGGGACACACGGACAAACAACAGACAGAAGACGUACUGGCCGCUGGACUCCGCUGCCUCCCCCAUCUCCCCGCCAUCUGCGCCCGGAGGAUGAGCCCAGCCUUCAGGGCCAUGGAUGUGGAGCCCCGCGCCAAAGGCGUCCUUCUGGAGCCCUUUGUCCACCAGGUCGGGGGGCACUCAUGCGUGCUCCGCUUCAAUGAGACAACCCUGUGCAAGCCCCUGGUCCCAAGGGAACAUCAGUUCUACGAGACCCUCCCUGCUGAGAUGCGCAAAUUCACUCCCCAGUACAAAGGUGUGGUAUCUGUGCGCUUUGAAGAAGAUGAAGACAGGAACUUGUGUCUAAUAGCAUAUCCAUUGAAAGGGGACCAUGGAAUUGUGGACAUUGUAGAUAAUUCAGACUGUGAACCAAAAAGUAAGCUCCUAAGGUGGACAACAAACAAAAAACAUCAUGUCUUAGAAACAGAAAAGACCCCUAAGGACUGGGUGCGUCAGCACCGUAAAGAGGAGAAAAUGAAGAGCCAUAAGUUAGAAGAAGAAUUUGAGUGGCUAAAGAAAUCUGAAGUCUUGUACUACACUGUAGAGAAGAAGGGGAAUAUAAGUUCCCAGCUUAAACACUAUAACCCUUGGAGCAUGAAAUGUCACCAGCAACAGUUACAGAGAAUGAAGGAGAAUGCAAAGCAUCGGAACCAGUACAAAUUUAUCUUACUGGAAAACCUGACUUCCCGCUACGAGGUGCCUUGUGUCCUUGACCUCAAGAUGGGCACACGACAACAUGGUGAUGAUGCUUCAGAGGAGAAGGCAGCCAACCAGAUCCGAAAAUGUCAGCAGAGCACAUCUGCAGUCAUUGGUGUGCGUGUGUGUGGCAUGCAGGUGUACCAAGCAGGCAGUGGGCAGCUCAUGUUCAUGAACAAGUACCAUGGACGGAAGCUAUCGGUGCAGGGCUUCAAGGAGGCACUUUUCCAGUUCUUCCACAAUGGGCGGUACCUGCGCCGUGAACUCCUGGGCCCUGUGCUCAAGAAGCUGACUGAGCUCAAGGCAGUGUUGGAGCGACAGGAGUCCUACCGCUUCUACUCAAGCUCCCUGCUGGUCAUUUAUGAUGGCAAGGAGCGGCCCGAAGUGGUCCUGGACUCAGAUGCUGAGGAUUUGGAGGACCUGUCAGAGGAAUCAGCUGAUGAGUCUGCUGGUGCCUAUGCCUACAAACCCAUCGGCGCCAGCUCUGUAGAUGUGCGCAUGAUCGACUUUGCACACACCACCUGCAGGCUGUAUGGCGAGGACACCGUGGUGCAUGAGGGCCAGGAUGCUGGCUAUAUCUUCGGGCUCCAGAGCCUGAUAGACAUUGUCACAGAGAUAAGUGAGGAGAGUGGGGAGUGAGCUUGCUAGCUGCUCCAGUACUUGAGAGCGACUCUGUGUCCCAGGCACAGCUGUGCUGCGUCAGGGAGGAAGCCAGUAUGGCCAGGUGGUGGCUCCUGCAGCCUGGAGCUGAUGUGCAGUGGCCUCUGUGAGCCCCAGCCUGAGCCAGUCCCAGCUGUGCUUGGAGUCUUUAUUUAUUUUAACUAUUUCUUCAACAUUCCACAUUUGAUGAUGAUACCUCUUUCUUCCCUGAGUGUAUAUGUUCUAAUACAAAUCUUUUUGUUUAUUGUA